GAUCGAUGCUUUCUUCCGCGCCCCGAGAGCCGCCAUUUUUGAGAGCGGGGGAGGAGAGACAAGCAGGGGCGGCAGAGGCUCAACGGGAUGCUGACUGGGUUUUGCUUUUCGUCCCAGCCUUGUGGGGCCGGGACGGAAGAACCCAUCAAAGCCCUUCCUCCCGCCGCCUCUCCGGAAUGAGGUCUCAGCACCCGCGCGGGACAGCACCCUUCCUCCUGCGACAGAGCCCAAGAAGAGGCCGAAACCGAGACCAUGCCAGGGAAGCUGAAGGUGAAAAUCGUGGCCGGGCGCCAUUUGCCAGUGAUGGACCGUGCUAGUGACCUGACUGAUGCCUUCGUGGAGGUAAAAUUUGGUAAUACCACCUUUAAAACAGAUGUGUACCUUAAGUCACUCAACCCUCAGUGGAACUCGGAGUGGUUUAAAUUUGAGGUGGAUGAUGAAGACUUACAAGAUGAACCUUUACAGAUCACAGUUCUUGACCAUGAUACUUACAGUGCAAAUGAUGCCAUUGGUAAAGUGUACAUUGAUAUUGAUCCUUUACUGUAUAGUGAAGCUGCAACAGUCAUCUCAGGAUGGUUUCCAAUUUAUGACACCAUACAUGGUAUCCGUGGGGAAAUCAAUGUAGUUGUCAAAGUAGACCUCUUCAAUGAUUUAAAUCGAUUUAGGCAGUCAUCAUGUGGAGUCAAAUUCUUUUGCACAACGUCUAUUCCAAAAUGCUAUAGAGCUGUGAUAAUUCAUGGAUUUGUAGAAGAACUUGUGGUCAAUGAAGACCCAGAAUAUCAGUGGAUUGAUCGAAUUCGCACACCAAGGGCAUCAAAUGAGGCCAGACAGAGACUCAUUUCGUUAAUGUCAGGUGAGCUGCAGAGGAAGAUUGGCUUGAAAGUACUUGAAAUGAGAGGAAAUGCAGUUGUGGGGUACUUACAGUGUUUCGAUCUGGAGGGCGAGUCUGGGUUAGUGGUGCGAGCCAUAGGAACGGCGUGUACUCUGGAUAAAUUAAGUAGCCCAGCAGCAUUCCUUCCUGCAUGUAAUUCCCCAUCCAAAGAAAUGAAGGAGAUUCCCUUCAAUGAAGAUCCCAAUCCCAAUACUCACUCAUCAGGACCCUCAACCCCUCUGAAAAACCAAACUUAUUCCUUUUCACCUUCCAAGUCCUACAGUCGACAGUCCUCUUCUUCUGACACAGAUUUGAGUUUGACACCCAAAACUGCACCUUACCCACAGGGACCUAGGAUUUACCUGUGUCCCAGCUCCCCCUCUCUCUCUUGUGGUUCCCUUCAUCUUAAAAAGUCCUGUCUCCUCCUCUCGGAAUCUAGCCUUACCCCUCAUCAUUCUAGCCUUGUCAGCCCAGUUCUGAGGAAAAGUGUUUCUUUCAGUGAAGAGCUGUUCCUGGCUGCUUCUGGAAUGGGAAGUGGUAGUGCUGGAAAAGAAGGGGGGCCCUUUAAAGCUCUUUUAAGACAACAGACUCAAUCAGCGUUGGAACAGAGGGAAUUUCCAUUUUUUACCUUGACGGCAUUUCCUCCUGGAUUCCUUGUACACGUUGGGGGUGUAGUUAGUGCACGUUCUGUGAAGCUUUUGGAUCGUAUCCACAAUCCUGCCUUUGUCGGAAUUAUGGGUAACACAAGAUCUUACAAACUGCUAGACUGGAAUAGUUUCAAUUCAGGAGUUCAAGAUGUAAGUUUUGAUGGGAAAUUUAUCUUCUUCAAGAGGUUAGCAGUUGGAAUGUUACUUUCAGAUGAACCAGAAACUCGAGAUGCAUGGUGGGCAGAAAUCAGACAAGAAAUAAAAUCACAUGCUAAAGCAUUAGGCUGUCAUGCUGUAGUGGGCUACAGUGAAUCAACUAGCAUCUGUGAAGAGGUCUGCAUUUUAUCUGCAUCUGGCACAGCGGCUGUACUGAAUCCUAGAUUUCUGCAGGAUGGCACCGUGGAAGGCUGUUUGGAACAGAGGCUUGAAGAAAAUUUGCCUACACGUUGUGGAUUUUGUCAUAUACCAUAUGAUGAACUGAAUAUGCCAUUUCCAGCUCAUCUCACAUAUUGCUAUAACUGCAGGAAACAAAAAGUUCCUGAUGUUCUGUUUACAACUAUAGACCUCCCAACAGAUGCAACAGUUAUUGGAAAAGGUUGUCUUAUUCAAGCAAGGUUAUGUCGCUUAAAAAAGAAAGCACAGGCAGAAGCAAAUGCUACAGCUAUCAGUAAUCUCUUGCCAUUUAUGGAAUAUGAAGUGCAUACUCAGCUAAUGAAUAAACUAAAACUCAAAGGAAUGAAUGCUUUGUUUGGACUAAGAAUUCAGAUCACAGUGGGUGAAAAUAUGUUGAUGGGCUUAGCGUCUGCCACAGGUGUGUAUUUAGCAGCUUUACCAACUCCUGGUGGUAUUCAGAUUGCUGGGAAGACUCCUAAUGAUGGCUCAUAUGAACAACACAUCUCUCAUAUGCAGAAGAAGAUAAAUGACACAAUUGCUAAAAACAAAGAGUUAUAUGAAAUCAAUCCUCCAGAGAUAUCUGAAGAGAUUAUAGGAUCACCCAUCCCAGAACCUAGGCAACGCUCAAGACUUCUAAGAUCUCAAUCAGAAAGCUCGGAUGAAGUUACAGAAUUAGACCUUUCACAUGGGAAAAAAGAUGCUUUUGUUUUGGAGAUUGAUGACACAGAUGCCAUGGAAGAUGUCCAUUCUCUACUUACUGAUGUUCCUCCUCCUUCAGGCUUUUAUAGUUGUAAUACAGAAAUUAUGCCCGGUAUAAAUAAUUGGACCUCUGAAAUACAGAUGUUCACUUCAGUAAGAGUAAUCAGAUUAAGCAGCCUCAACCUGACUAAUCAAGCUCUCAAUAAGAACUUUAAUGAUCUCUGUGAAAAUUUGCUCAAGAGCCUGUACUUUAAACUACGAUCUAUGAUCCCCUGCUGCCUUUGCCAUGUAAAUUUUACAGUAUCUCUGCCUGAAGAUGAAUUAAUUCAGGUUACAGUCACGGCAGUCGCAAUCACUUUUGACAAAAAUCAGGCUUUACAAACCACAAAAACCCCUGUUGAAAAGUCAUUGCAAAGAGCCUCAACAGAUAAUGAAGAACUUUUACAAUUUCCACUGGAACUGUGUUCAGAUUCACUUCCUUCUCAUCCUUUUCCACCAGCUAAAGAACACCUGGAGAGUGCAAGUUCUAACUCAGGUAUACCAGCUGCACAGAGAGCAACGUCAGUUGAUUACAGUUCCUUUGCAGACAGAUGCAGCAGCUGGAUAGAGCUCAUUAAACUGAAAGCUCAGACCAUAAGGCGUGGAUCAAUUAAGACAACCAUGACAGUUGAAAAAGCAAGUCCAGUGGGUGAUGGAAAUUUCCGGAAUCGUUCUGCUCCACCUUGUGCAAAUUCCACAGUUGGGGUUGUUAAGAUGACACCUCUUUCUUUUAUUCCUGGAGCAAAAAUAACUAAGUAUCUUGGGAUAAUUAACAUGUUUUUUAUUCGAGAGACUACUUCUCUUCGGGAGGAAGGAGGAGUCAGUGGUUUUCUCCAUGCUUUUAUUGCUGAAGUGUUUGCAAUGGUGAGAGCUCAUGUUGCUGCAUUAGGAGGGAAUGCUGUUGUCUCCUACAUAAUGAAGCAGUGUGUCUUCAUGGAGAAUCCAAAUAAAAACCAGGCACAGUGUCUUAUAAAUGUAAGUGGUGAUGCAGUGGUUUUUGUUCGUGAAUCUGACUUAGAAGUGGUGUCAUCUCAGCAACCUACUACCAACUGCCAGUCAUCAUGUACUGAAGGCGAAGUUACAACCUGAGGAAAAUUAGGAAAAAAGAGCUCAACUAAAUGAAAUUCAUCAAUCUCUGUUAUUUUGUCAUUAAUUAUCUUCUUAGACUUAAAAUUGAACUUGAGAUAAAUAAGGAAGAAUUGAGUAGAUUUGAUUUGCCUGGAGUCUUUUGGAGGCAUGAGAAUUUUCUAAUCUUGACAUUUUGUUUGCCUGUUCUAGACAGGCCCUGUGGGGUCUUGACCCUUCAGUAAGUUAAGAUAAAUUUUUAAAAGAACCGUAGCAAAGAUGGAACCUUUGUAAUUUAUGUUGAUUUUAAUAAAAUCAUAAUUUAAAAAAUGAAAUGGGAAGAUUGUCAGGAAAUUAGGAUAGCUACUCUAGUAUAAUUUAGAAAAACUAAGCAAGAGAUUCUCCAGUUGCUAGUGAGUAAGCACUCUGAUUUGAGAAAUGUGUGGGGACAAUGGAGAAAAGUUUUCAGAAAACUGCUAUGUAGAUUUCUGAAUGUGUUGUAUUUUGCUGAGGAAUUCGGUAACAACUGAAAGGGAAAAGUGCUUCAGCCAUCUUUUGAAAACAAGUUAAAAUUCUGGAACUUGUAUCUGUAAUACAUCCUAACUCUUGUAAAAGAAAAUAAUUUAUCAUAGCUGGUGUCCUUUCAUUGAAAGUUGUAAUACUGUCUCUAAGGAGGGAGGAAAAGAUUAUUAUAUAAUUUUAUAACUGGCAACAUUUGAGUUAGUAUUGACUUUGUCUAAAAGAGGCUUGACUUCAACUGGGAUAAAAAUGUCAGUGAAUUUUGUUAAAGUAGUAAAAAUGCAGUUGACUUAGUAGGAACAUAAAAUUAUUUCCUAAUAAGAUAAUAUUGCACUCCUACCAAAUAAACAGGAUUUUAGUAAUAUCUGAGGGAUUGUUGAUGGUGAGUUAGACUGUAUUUGGCAUAGAAUUUGGAAAUGUAACUUGAAUGUAAAUAUGCUGCAAAAUGUUGAAUGUAUACAUAGAAAGACUUUUUCUGUCGACGCCAAAUGCCCGUUGUAAAUGAACCUUAAAUAUUACAUUCCUCCUUUGCACAAUAAUAUUUCUUUAUAACACUUAUGAUUUUUUCCCCCAGGACAACAAACUGCCCUUAAGAGUCAUUUCCUUGUUAUCACAGGUGUCAAUAUUUUUCUGUAUUUUGUUUAUAAUUUUAUUUUUUAAAUAAAAAGUGUAUAAAAAUAAA